GGGAACCAAAAAAGGCUGGAAGAACAUGAAGAUGGAGCAGUCAUAAACCACCCACUCAAGGACCAUCUCCUUCAGGACCAUCCACACGAGACUCAGAUUGUCUGAAUUGAGCUAUCGCAACUUAAUGCUAAAAGCUCCUUAAAGCUACAGAUUUAUGACAUAGUUCCUUCCAAAAUAUUACAUCAUAAAUCAUUGAGAAGAUUAAAAAAAAACACUUGAAGAAAUUGUAGUUUUAAACAUCUCUGCAUAUAUUUUGGAUAGCUACUAGGUUACUUUAACUGUCAUUAAGGAGCACAGACUUACUGAAGCUUUACUGGACAGAAUCCUGGGAAAUCGAUAUCAUUAUAAGGUUAUAUUUCCCAGUUAGCGGGUGAAGGGCUGGAGACCUUAUUGCAGUCAUGGCUUUCACAAAUUACAGCAGUCUGAAUCGAGCUCAGCUAACCUUUGAAUAUCUGCACACAAAUUCGUAAGUAUCCUCUAGGUGCCACUGAGGUAACCAGUAACUCGUUCCUUGAUAUUAUAUGGAAAUCGUUUCCCCAGAAAAUUUUGCUUUUUCACUUUUUGAGAUGUAUCCCACUGGAGUGAAAUGUGUCACUGGAUAUCUUGAGCUCUGUAUUGAAGAACUGAGAUCAGUGAAAUACUUGUUGCUAAUCCAGAAGAAUCUGAUUUUUGUUUAUUGGAUCAAAAUUUUCUAAAUGCAAACUUUAGUUAUUUGAAGUCAAUAUGUUGAGUUGUUUCAUUCAAGUGUUUAUAGGAAUCCAACAAAUACUGCUCUAUUGGAUCGCCAAAUGUUGGACUAUUUUAGUAUCAACCGUUUCCCCUCUGUAGUGACAACGUCCUAAACAGUUAGGUUUAUAACAAGUGUUUACUUUCUAACAAGAAAACAGAAGACAUUUAAAUGACAACUUUCAAGAAGAAAAUUUUUAUUUUUUCAGAAGUUGGCAUUAUCUUCCUGGCAGAUUGCUCACAUCCAAUAUUAUUUGUAUAUGCUAAACAGGAAACGGCAACUUGUUUAUAUCUCUAUUUAGAUAGUCUUUCCCCAAAAUUUCCACAGAAACAUACAGUGUUCAUGGUUCUUGAGUUCAUGAAGGAGUAAUCUAAUCACUCCAACAUGGUCUGGAAUGUUUCAGGUUUAAUCCAUAUGCCCACUCUCUUGGAGGCUGUCCAGUAGCGUCAAAACUUUAGUGUUUUAAUACAUUCACCUGUUACUUUUGAGAUGAAGUUCACCUUUCUUGGAUCACAUGCAAAGGAUGUUUAGGUCUGUGAAGAAAAGAAUUUCUAGGCCGGGUGCUGUGGCUCACGCCUGUAAUCCCAGCACUUUGGGAGGCCGAGAACCACUCACGAAUUCUUGUUUGGUGCCCUUGCUGAACUGGUUGAUAAUGCAAGAGAUGCUGAUGCCACCAGAAUAGAUAUUUAUGCAGAAAGACGAGAGGACCUUCGAGGAGGAUUUAUGCUUUGCUUUUUGGAUGAUGGAGCAGGAAUGGAUCCAAGUGAUGCUGCCAGUGUGAUCCAGUUUGGGAAGUCGGCCAAGCGAACACCUGAGUCUACUCAGAUUGGGCAGUACGGGAAUGGGUUAAAAUCGGGCUCAAUGCGCAUUGGGAAGGAUUUUAUCCUGUUCACCAAGAAGGAAGACACCAUGACCUGCCUCUUCCUGUCUCGCACGUUUCAUGAGGAAGAAGGCAUUGAUGAAGUGAUAGUCCCACUGCCCACCUGGAAUGCUCGGACCCGGGAACCUGUCACAGACAAUGUAGAGAAAUUUGCCAUUGAGACAGAACUCAUCUAUAAGUACUCUCCAUUCCGCACUGAGGAGGAAGUGAUGACCCAGUUUAUGAAGAUUCCUGGGGACAGCGGAACAUUGGUGAUCAUCUUCAAUCUCAAACUCAUGGAUAAUGGAGAGCCAGAACUAGACAUAAUCUCAAAUCCAAGAGAUAUCCAGAUGGCAGAGACGUCCCCAGAGGGCACGAAGCCAGAGCGGCGCUCGUUCCGUGCCUAUGCCGCUGUGCUCUAUAUUGAUCCCCGGAUGAGGAUCUUCAUCCAUGGGCACAAGGUGCAGACCAAGAGGCUCUCCUGCUGCCUGUACAAGCCCAGGAUGUACAAGUACACGUCAAGCCGUUUCAAGACCCGUGCGGAGCAGGAGGUGAAGAAAGCAGAGCACGUAGCAAGGAUUGCUGAAGAGAAGGCGCGGGAGGCAGAGAGCAAAGCUCGGACAUUAGAAGUACGCCUAGGUGGAGACCUCACGCGGGACUCCAGGGUGAUGUUGCGACAGGUCCAGAACAGAGCCAUCACUCUGCGCAGAGAAGCCGAUGUCAAGAAGAGGAUCAAGGAGGCCAAGCAGCGAGCACUUAAAGAACCUAAGGAACUGAAUUUUGUUUUUGGUGUCAACAUUGAACACCGGGAUCUGGAUGGCAUGUUCAUCUACAACUGUAGCCGACUGAUCAAAAUGUAUGAGAAAGUGGGCCCACAGCUGGAAGGGGGCAUGGCAUGUGGCGGGGUUGUUGGGGUUGUUGAUGUGCCCUACCUGGUCCUGGAGCCUACACACAACAAACAGGACUUUGCUGAUGCCAAGGAGUACCGGCACCUGCUCCGAGCAAUGGGGGAGCACCUGGCGCAGUAUUGGAAGGAUAUUGCCAUCGCCCAGAGGGGAAUCAUCAAGUUCUGGGAUGAGUUUGGCUACCUCUCUGCCAACUGGAACCAGCCCCCAUCCAGUGAGCUGCGUUACAAACGCCGGAGAGCUAUGGAAAUCCCCACCACCAUCCAGUGCGAUUUGUGUCUGAAAUGGAGAACCCUCCCCUUCCAGCUGAGUUCUGUGGAAAAAGAUUACCCUGACACCUGGGUUUGCUCCAUGAACCCUGAUCCUGAACAGGACCGGUGUGAGGCUUCUGAACAAAAGCAGAAGGUUCCCCUGGGAACAUUCAGAAAGGACAUGAAGACGCAGGAAGAGAAGCAGAAACAACUGACAGAGAAAAUUCGCCAGCAGCAGGAGAAGCUGGAGGCCCUUCAGAAAACCACACCCAUCCGCUCCCAAGCAGACCUGAAGAAAUUGCCCUUGGAAGUGACCACCAGACCUUCCACUGAGGAACCUGUGCGUAGACCUCAGCGUCCUCGGUCGCCCCCUUUACCUGCUGUGAUCAGGAACGCCCCCAGCAGACCCCCUUCUUUGCCAACUCCUAGACCAGCCAGCCAGCCCCGAAAGGCUCCUGUCAUCAGCAGUACCCCAAAGCUCCCUGCUUUGGCAGCCCGGGAGGAGGCCAGCACAUCUAGGCUGCUCCAGCCACCUGAGGCACCCCGAAAGCCUGCCAACACUCUCGUCAAGACUGCAUCCCGACCUGCCCCUCUGGUGCAGCAACUGUCACCAUCUUUACUGCCCAACUCCAAGAGCCCUCGGGAGGUUCCUUCUCCCAAAGUCAUCAAGACUCCAGUGGUGAAGAAGACAGAGUCACCCAUCAAACUCUCCCCGGCUACCCCUAGUCGGAAGCGGAGUGUCGCAGUUUCUGAUGAGGAAGAAGUUGAGGAGGAAGCUGAGAGGAGGAAGGAGAGGUGCAAGCGGGGCAGAUUUGUUGUGAAGGAGGAAAAGAAGGACUCGAAUGAGCUCUCAGACAGUGCUGGGGAAGAGGACUCGGCUGACCUCAAGAGAGCUCAGAAAGAUAAAGGGCUGCACGUGGAGGUGCGUGUGAACAGGGAGUGGUACACGGGCCGUGUCACAGCCGUGGAGGUGGGCAAGCAUGUGGUGCGGUGGAAGGUGAAGUUUGACUACGUGCCCACAGACACGACACCAAGAGACCGCUGGGUGGAGAAAGGCAGUGAGGAUGUGCGGCUGAUGAAACCCCCUUCUCCGGAACAUCAGAGCCUUGAUACACAACAGGAGGGCGGGGAGGAGGAGGUGGGCCCUGUGGCCCAGCAGGCCAUAGCUGUCGCAGAGCCCUCCACUUCCGAAUGCCUCCGCAUUGAGCCUGACACCACUGCCCUGAGCACCAAUCACGAGACCAUCGACCUGCUUGUCCAGAUCCUCCGGAAUUGUUUACGGUACUUCCUGCCUCCAAGUUUCCCCAUCUCCAAGAAGCAGCUGAGUGCUAUGAAUUCAGAUGAGCUAAUAUCUUUUCCUCUGAAGGAGUACUUCAAGCAAUAUGAAGUAGGGCUCCAAAACCUGUGCAAUUCCUACCAGAGCCGUGCUGACUCCCGGGCCAAGGCCUCCGAGGAAAGCCUGCGCACCUCCGAGAGGAAGCUCCGCGAGACGGAGGAGAAGCUGCAGAAGCUGAGGACCAACAUCGUGGCACUCCUGCAAAAGGUGCAGGAGGACAUAGACAUCAACACAGAUGAUGAGCUGGACGCCUACAUUGAGGACCUCAUCACCAAGGGGGACUGAAGGCAGGAGAGAGAGCAGCUCCCCUGCCCACCUGCCCCUCAACCCUGUAGCUGCAGGGGGAGGGGACUUCAUUCAUGGGUUGGUGGUCGCACCUUGGUUUGACUUACACGGGACAUUUGUGUUUUUGGAGGAAAAGAUACCCUGAUUCUUUGAAUCUUCCUUAAGUUUAUAAAUAUUUAUUUUUUAAAAGAAGAUGCUGUGCCUGUGAGACCAUACUUUUUUUUUUUUUUUUUUUUUUUUUUUUUUUUUUUUGGUGACUGCAAAGGACAGAGAACCUUUCCACUUUGGCCAUACUGGGUUGCUAAGCCGGAGCCAUUUCAGCUCCUGGCUCCUCAAGAUAACGGCGAGUCCAGUGCCAUCUUGGAGAAGCUCCAGGGGCAGGGCUGACUUUUCUCCUACAGGAGGAACAAUGUGGGGAUCUGAGGGAUGGGAGGGAGACUUCCCCCUAGAGUGGUGGUCCUGCUGGGGGCUCAUAUCCAGGGACCCAAAAGGGGGGCUGUGUAGGAGGUUCCACAUUGGAGGGGCUCUCUCUCUCGCAGCUGUCAGAGUUGGUCCUGGCUGUGGCGUCCAAACAGCUUGAGGGAAAAAGAUCCUGUCUAACCACCUCAUCUACUACUCAAGUUCUUUCUGAAGGAGGGAUUUCUUCAGUUAACCAUGGACAGUGAGGUUUCUCACCACAGUAACUUGAGUCCAGGUUGAGGGGGAGACAGAUCUGUGGUAAAUCUCUGACUUGGGCAGCACACUGAGUGUGGAACCCCACAGGACUCCUUAGGGAAGGAGCUUGUGUGUGAAAGAACCCCUGGGGCUGAGCUGGUGACCUCCAUGUGUGGGUGCAGCAGGGCCUUGGAUGGUGCCAAUUGAUCUGGACAGCCUGUUGAUGCUUUUCUACUUCCACCCUUCGGCCUGGCCCCACUGAGCCCCAUCAAGGUGCCUGAAGAGGGGGCCAGUGAGAUCCCGUGGCCACAGGGACUCCAGAGGCAUCUCUGCAGGAAGCACACCAUGCCUUCCCUCCAUGUUCCAUCACGGCGCCACAAUCUGUGUCCCUUAACUUCUCAGGGUCAAAGACAAAGGCAAGCGUUGCUGAAUUUUCUCUUUAAUGGCCAUUGGAAGAGUCUGGUUCAGUUUUUCCCAACUCUCUUCCCACUCGUAUUUGGGGCCUCUGGGUUUUCUGAAGGCACAAGGACUGUGACUUUGUACCACUAACCUGUGGUUCAAACCUGGGUGUGUUUCUGGCAUCUCCCUAACCCAGAUCAGCAAUGGCCACCCUGCUCCUCUGAGGUCAGCAGAAGACUGGGAAGCAGAGGUGAGGGAUGCAGGCCACACUGGAAUGGGAAGUCUUUUCCCCACUGGAUGUGCCUGUCUGGUGGGUUUUGGACCUUCCCAGACUACAUCUCUAGGAGAGGCCUGUUUGGAGUAGUACACUGAGAGACCCUGGCCUCUUCUGCUGGAAGACUGUCCAAGUCUUGGGGUUUCUUGAGCUGGUGAUUCCUCUGCCAUCCUGCUCUCUCUCUUCAUCUCAGGCAGCAUGGGGUCCACUUUUGUCCCCAAACCUAAUGUUUUAAUCCAAAUGCAAAUUGGUUCCACAUUUUUACUGGAGGGUAAUCAGUUUUUAAAAUUCACACACAUGUAAUCGAAACGCAAUACUAUAAAGUUCUACUGGUGAGACUCCUGAA